AUUCCUAUAAAGCUAAAAAUCGAGGCGGGGCCGAGAGGCUGCGGCGGCUGACUAGGUUUUCGGACCGCGGCGCGGCGGGGAAGAGAGACUGCGGCGGGAGGGCCAGGCCGUGGGAGAGACGCGGGAAAGUGCGGGUCGCAGAGGCACUUGACCACCCCGCCCUAGGCCGACCCGGCGGACGCGGCGUCUGGUGUGCGGGCGCUGGGGCGGGUCCCAGGUCUCCCCGCUGCGCUGCUUGAGGCUCGGCCAUGGCCCAGCAGAGAGCCCUGCCCCAGAGCAAGGAGACGCUGCUGCAGUCCUACAACAAGCGGCUGAAGGACGACAUUAAGUCCAUCAUGGACAACUUCACCGAGAUCAUCAAGACCGCCAAGAUUGAGGACGAGACGCAGGUGUCACGGGCCACUCAGGGUGAACAGGACAAUUACGAGAUGCAUGUGCGAGCCGCCAACAUCGUCCGAGCCGGCGAGUCCCUGAUGAAGCUGGUGUCCGACCUCAAGCAGUUCCUGAUCCUCAAUGACUUCCCCUCCGUGAACGAGGCCAUUGACCAGCGCAACCAGCAGCUGCGCACACUGCAGGAGGAGUGCGACCGGAAGCUCAUCACGCUGCGAGACGAGAUCUCCAUUGACCUCUACGAGCUGGAGGAGGAGUAUUACUCGUCCAGCUCAAGCCUUUGCGAAGCUAAUGACCUGCCUCUGUGCGAAGCUUACGGGAGGCUGGACCUCGACACAGACUCUGCUGAUGGCCUCUCGGCCCCUCUGCUGGCGUCCCCGGAGCCCAGUGCUGGCCCCCUACAGGUGGCAGCCCCUGCCCACUCCCAUGCUGGUGGCCCUGGCCCCACUGAGCACGCCUGAGCCUCCGGGGCCACGCUUCGUUCUCAGGAACAAAACCUGAGGCAGCCCUUUGGAUGCCCUCACAGCCUUGCUUCUCUCAGCCUAGGUUCCCAUUUGGGGACUUCAGGACCCCAGAGCCACUAGGACUUCCUUGGGAAGCCCGUUAGCCCAGGGUGGGUCCCGCCAGGACAGUAGGGAAACAGUUGUUUCCCUAGCCAUUUCCGAAUAGCCCAUCAUUCCGAGUCAUCAUCUCUGUUUGCUGCCUUCCUGGCCAGCCAGGUGGAAGAAAGUUUCCAAGCUAGGUCUGGCCCGUUGGGGAUCUCAGCAGUGGGGCAGGAGGGUGCCUGAUUUCGGGGAGUCCUGACCCGAGCCUGUUGUCAGAGUUGGGAGGGGCUCUGAGCAGUGUUGGGCAGGCCGGGUCUCCCAUCCCGAGGCCAGCGUUCCUGUGCAGAGCCCCAUCCACUGGUUCUUGCCCUGAGCCACAUAUGUCUGUGCCAUGGGCUGAGUGCCACGACAGGCCCGUGUGACAGCUGCUGCCCACGCAUGUGGAAGCUAGGUGGGACUCAUUCCUAAUUCUGCCGUUGUAAUGAGACUUGAUUAAAACACCGCCACUUUUUUGCAUUGCUGCUCUUUCUUCCUCAUUCCUUGUCAGUCCAGGACCAUCCUUGGUCUCCCAGCAGUUGUCCGAGCAGCAGCUCCUCAGCUCUGCCUGGACAGCCUGGCCCAAGGUCACUCUCUCCUCAUUGGCACCUGGUAGGUCCCCAGUAUUCAGUGAAUGGACCUGCUGCCAUCAUUGCACAUCCAGGCACCUGUGCCUCUGCUGGCAUCUCAUCCUCACUGCUACCAGAGCCGGUGCUCCUAGUGCCGGUAUUUUAGAGAGGAGAGGAUGUGGACUUAGAAGGGGUGAGGUGUACCACGGCCACAGAGCUAGGAAGUGAAGUGGCAGGAAUCAGAACUUGAACCUGAUGGAAGUCUAGACCCAGUGUCUUUUGGUGCCAGGCUCACCUUAGAAAUGCAGAAGUCACAACACUGGGCAGGAAGUGUGGGGGGAGCACAGUUCGUCCACAGGAAGUGUGGGGGAGCACCCCACCCCAGUUCCUCCAGCACCAUCCAUGUGCUUCAUCUUCUCAUGGGGGAGGCCAUCAUCUUUCCCGAUGUAUGAAUGAGGUGACAGCCCAGGAUCCAGCCUUGGGGACAGGUAAGAACACAGCUGACCCAUCACCACCUGAACCAGAGAACCCCACAGCCAAGCAGAAGGCACCAGACAGACAGGAGCUUGAGGCCCAGUCCUGGCUCUGGACCUGGCUUCUGGGGUGGCCUAGGGAAGUUGCUUCCCCUCUGAGGGAGAAUUUCCCCAUUGAUACGUGUGGUGAUCUGUUCCCGCACUAUUUUAGCUGUGGAAAUGCCUUGUACUUAACCACUGAGGAAGAAAAAGAUUACAACCAGAUGGAAGCAUAUAUGAAGCGAGAGCCCGGAAGGAACUGGCCAGACUUUGUGGUGGGAUCCCACUUACCCUGUUCCUAAAAUCCUGAGCGAUAAGACCUGCCAUCAGCUUCAUUUUCUGCUUGGCCAGGACCAUCAUUCCCAUGUGAAAAUCAAGUUAUUUCUCCUUCUUAAAGCCAAGCCGCUCUGCUGACCUUUUUUCCUCUCCAGCUCAUGGCCUUGGCAGCAGAGCUCCACGGGGAAGCAGCUGAUAACCAUUUGCAGUUCUCUCUUGGGCCUACGUCAGACAGGUUUUGUCUCCAUGACUCUAGCAAAACUACACCUAUUAAGGUCACCAGUGGCCUCCACAUUGCUAAGCCCCGGCCCAUUCUCAGUCCAUGUAACUCUUUUAUCCCAAGCUUUUUAUUUUGAGGGCAGUGGAACUCAUGGAAGUACUUGUCAGUUUGCCUCUCUGAGCACAUUCUCCUUCGUCCAUCACCACAACCAGAAUGGAUGAUGAUUGCAUAUCCUCUGGUAUCUAGCUGUAUUCAGAUUUCUUCAGUUGUUCCCCAAAUAGUUUUUUUAAUGCCUAUUUUUUUUCUUUCUAGUCCAGAGGUCUUUUAUUUUUUUAACACCCACGAUGCCAUGAAUUCAUAGGGAAGAGGUUCCAGCAGCUCAGGCUCCUUCCCAUUGGUUCUCACAGUGUGCUGCUCUGGGUGGAGCAGGCUGGCGCUUCAGUUGAAUCCAGGUACCUUUCUCUUUGGCUUCCCUCUUUUUCUGAUCAUUUUCCUUCACGCGUUUCAGGAAGCUCUCUCGGCUCUUAGAGUGCUUAGUGUGCUGAAUAUGCACAUUCAUUCUCUUGGCAAGAAUCUUGCCCUUACUUGUUUACAACAGUGCCAACAGCAUGCUGGGGAACACUGUAGACUCUCCCAGUCUAGCCAUGGUGACAUUUGUGGGGCAUUCCUUUUUGAACAGUACCCAUUCCCUUGAUAUCUACAAUAUCACCUUUCUCAUCAAUUUGCAUAUACUUGGCCAAAGGAACAACUGCAUGUUUUCUGAAAGGCCUAGAGAACAUAUAUUGGGUGCCUCUCCUCUUUCCCUUUGUGUUCGUCAUUUUGGCGAAUUACUGGAAGGUGGCGGUUCCAGCUGAAAGGCUUUUAUGCCUGUUUUUAUUGUGUGUUGCAUUUGGUUGUUAUUUUGGAGUCUUAAAAUCUAAAACAGGACCAGGUCAGGCCCAGUGGCUCCUGCUGUAAUCCCAGCACUUUGAGAAGCCAAAGCGGGUGGAUCACUUGUGGUCAGAAGUUUUGAGACCAGCCUGGGCAACAUGGAGAAACCCCGUCUCUACUAAAAAGUAUAGAAAUCGGCCGGGCGCGGUGGCUUACGCCUGCAACCCCAGCACUUUGGGAGGCCAAGGCGGGCGGAUCACCUGAGGUCGGGAUUUCCAGACCAGCCUGACCAACAUGGAGAAACCCUGUCUCUACUAAAAAGUAUAGAAAUUGGCCGGGCGCGGUGGCUCACGCCUGUAAUCCCAGCACUUUGGGAGGCCGAGGCGGGCAGAUCACCUGAGGUCGGGAGUUCCAGACCAGCCUGACCAACAUGGAGAAACCCUGUCUCUACUAAAAAUACAAAAAUUAGCCGGGCGUGCUGGUCCAUGCCUAUAAUCCCAGCUACUUGGUAGGCGGAGGCAGGAGAAUCGCUUGAACCCGGGAGGCGGAGGUUGCAGUGAGCCGAGAUCGGGCCACUGCACUCCAGCUUGGGCAACAAGAGCGAAACUCCACCUCAAAAAAAAAAA